GCUCGUGGGCUCGGACGAGUACGGAGCGCCUGCAGGGACAGCCUGGUACGCGGCCCCCGCCCCUUCGUGCGCGCGCUGGGCCUAGCUGCCGCUCAGGGUCGGGGCUGACCCGUCACUUUCGGGAACCUCAGUCCCAGCAGCUUCUCUCCCUCAGCCGGCCCGCUCCUGGAGAGAGACAGAAACCCUUUUCUGUCGCGUCCUCUCCUUGCGAGCCGCAGGGGGACCGAGCGGAGGCUAUUGGAGCCGCAGCCCCAGACCAGGGCGCUUGACCCUCUCUCGGAACGGGGCGGGGAAGGGGCGCGAGUGACCUCGGGGAGGGAAGGGCACUGGCAGGAAAGGACGCAACUGCAGAUCGGUAGCCGGAGGCCGCCACGGGCCAAAGGAAUAACUGGGAAGGUGGAUGCGAGGCCAACGAAUCCUACCUUGAAACUCUGCUCGCCUGCUGGCUCUGCCACUCCAGCAUCUGAAAGGAGAUAAAGGCUCACUGAUGGCUCAGUUGGGAGCAGUUGUGGCUGUGGCUUCCAGUUUCUUUUGUGCAUCUCUCUUCUCAGCUGUGCACAAGAUAGAAGAGGGACAUAUUGGGGUAUAUUACAGAGGCGGUGCCCUGCUGACUUCGACCAGCGGCCCUGGUUUCCAUCUCAUGCUCCCUUUCAUCACAUCAUAUAAGUCUGUGCAGACCACACUCCAGACAGAUGAGGUGAAGAAUGUACCUUGUGGGACUAGUGGUGGUGUGAUGAUCUACUUUGACAGAAUUGAAGUGGUGAACUUCCUGGUCCCGAACGCAGUGUAUGAUAUAGUGAAGAACUAUACUGCUGACUAUGACAAGGCCCUCAUCUUCAACAAGAUCCACCACGAACUGAACCAGUUCUGCAGUGUGCACACGCUUCAAGAGGUCUACAUUGAGCUGUUUGAUCAGAUUGAUGAAAAUCUCAAACUGGCUUUGCAACAGGACCUGACCUCCAUGGCCCCUGGGCUGGUCAUUCAAGCUGUGCGGGUAACAAAGCCCAACAUACCAGAGGCAAUCCGCAGAAACUACGAGUUGAUGGAAAGUGAGAAGACAAAGCUUCUCAUUGCCGCCCAGAAACAGAAGGUGGUGGAAAAGGAAGCAGAGACAGAGCGGAAGAAGGCGCUCAUUGAGGCAGAAAAAGUGGCCCAGGUGGCUGAGAUCACCUACGGGCAGAAGGUGAUGGAGAAGGAGACUGAGAAGAAGAUUUCAGAAAUUGAAGAUGCUGCAUUUCUGGCCCGGGAGAAGGCAAAGGCAGAUGCUGAGUGCUACACUGCUAUGAAAAUAGCCGAAGCCAAUAAGCUGAAGCUAACCCCUGAAUAUCUGCAGCUGAUGAAGUACAAGGCCAUUGCUUCCAACAGCAAGAUUUACUUUGGCAAAGACAUUCCUAACAUGUUCAUGGACUCUGCGGGCAGUGUGAGCAAGCAGUUUGAGGGGCUAGCUGACAAGCUAAGCUUUGGCUUAGAAGAUGAACCCUUGGAGACGGCCACUAAGGAGAAUUGAAAAAAACUUGAUAUGACUGCAAAUGAUACUUAAGCAGAUCUUUAUUUUUUAAGAUGAAUCAGAAUGUUCCUCCCUCCCCGACUACCUUCUCUGACUGUCUUCCAGUUACUGUGGUGAAAAAGAAGAAAUGAACUUAAAUCCACUCCCUUUCUAGGGAAAGGAGGGUGGGGACUGAUGAUGGGGGGUUUUAUUUCAGGUAAGCAGUUUAUAUGACUUCCAAUAAGAUUUGUAAAUCAUGGGCUUGACCUUUGACCUCUAGACACUAAUUUUAUCCUUUGAGGCUGGCUUAAUUAGGGAUGCUGUCAUUAAGGAGAGGGAGAAAUGUAGAGUGUUACCUCCAACUCAUUUGAUUUCCCUUACUUGGGAAAAUGCAGUCCAGUGUUCUCACCUCUGCCUCCAAGGUAGGAGAUGUCUGUGGGUGAGGCUCAGCAACUGAGCAAAUAUGUGCCUGUGAGUUUGCCAGUAGAGCUGUGAAGAAACAGCUGCAGAGAACAUUUGACCUUCCUGGCAUUCUUGUCUGCAUGUGUGUGAGUUAUUUUAGAGGUGUGCUUUCUUGAGCCCUCAUAAGGAAGUACUGGUGCUAGGUUUUGCAAGAUUUUGUAUACACUUUGCUCCUUGCCCUAGGGCUCAGAGUGGUGGUUUCUGACUACAUUUCUAGAGUCAGAGCUUGAUCACCACAACUCAAUUAUUUCGGCAUCUUUUCACCUAUGCUGUGAUUUGUUUUUUUUUUUUCUUCUCAAAAAUUCUGUUCAUUGGUUCCACUCAGCAUCAAGAAGACAGGGACAAACAACUCAAGUGUCUUAACAGCUGCUGGAGUGGGAUCCUUGUUAUCUCUUAGCCACUGCAGGACCUGCCUGACAGGUUAUGUGUGCACCUCGAGAUGAAGUGUCUUUCUAUUAUUGUAGAGAUUCUGUAGUGAAGAGGUCUGACACCAUGUGUGGAGGAGGAGGAACGAUCAGUCAAGAGAUGUCCUGGUCUUAAUGCCUGUGGCUUGUGCUGGGAGUGGGUCUGACUUAGUGAUAAAAGGACUCUAUUCACUAAGUAGCCUGUGUUUUUAAAUCCAGGGCUGCAGGCAGCAACGCAAGUCAGGCUGAACAUUCAGUCUCCAGAGACAGCUGUGUGGAGCAAAUCAGAGUUCAUGCCCAAGUCCCCAGGUUGGAAUGGCUGUGCCAAAAUCCAUUCAAAGGGUUUUCUUUUUCAUUACUAGGUCAGAACAUUUUGAGUCACCUUGGGAGAUUCAGGAUGGGGAGAGCAAAUUUGAACAAAAGGUUUUUCUUAUAUCCUGAGAUUGAGGGGUAGGGGGUGUCCAACCUGUAUAGCCCAUGGGUUGUGUCUAGAAUUAAGUGGAGGGCAGCUAUCUGGAGUUAACUUGCAAGCAUAUUGGUGCCCUCCAUGACCACCUCUGGCUUAGGACUUGGCCCUGUUAUGAGCUGACCCCCACCCCCCACCCCCCACCCCCCCCCCCCGCCAACUCCUAUACCCAUCUUCCCUAGGUGAAUCUGUGAAUGGUCCUUUCUGGCAGCAAUCCCUGCCUUCUUUUUGGGCCCAUGCCCAGACUUCUGGUUUAAGGAAUGGUCCCAGAGCUUGGGCCAGCUUGCUCAGAAGUUUUGGGAGCAUUGAGCCUGCCUAGAAAGAUACAGUGUUAGCUCCCCUUACUUCAAAGUUGCCCUUCUCUGUUCUGACUCCUGGGACUUCUGGUCCUGGGCACACUUUUUGCAGGCAACAAAAUGUGCCUGGGAGUGAUGGAUUUUAAUGUGCUCCAGAGUCCUUUCAGAAGGUGGUCAUUUCCCUUGGCCGGGCGCGGUGGCUCACACCUGUAAUCCCAGCACUUUGGGAGGCCAAGGCAGGCGGAUCACCUGAGGUUAGGAGUUCGAGACCACCCUGGCCAACAUGCGAAACCCCAUCUCUACGAAAAAUAGAAAUAUUAGCCGGGCAUGGUGUCAGGCACCUGUAAUCCCAGCUACUUGGGAGGCUGAGGCAGGAGAAUUGCUUGAACUCGGGAGGCAGAGGUUGCAGUGAGCCAAGAUCAUGCCAUCCCACUCUAGCUUGGGCAAUAGAGCAAGGCUCCGUCUCAAGAAAAGAAGGUCAUUUCCCAAGACUAGCAUAGGGAGUAUCCAUUUAAAAUACAUUCAUCUUCCUCCCAUUUCCGUGCUAUUAAUCACUUGUUAGAGCAACAUGACAUGCCCAGCAUCCCACUUCCCGAAAAUGUCUACUCCUUCUACUCUGAGCUCUUGUUGCCUAGACCUCAGAAAACACCAAUUCACCACAGUAGAACCGGGAGCAGGGAUAGCUCAGCUUCUCUGAAUAGCACACUUUGCUCAGGUCUUAACUUGAGGGCCUCUCCGGUACUAACAUCCUGCGAUAGCUUGUCCCAUGAGCACAGAAGAGCCUCAGUAGAGUCAAGUCCUGCUGCAGCUGCCCCACCCCAAGUUUCUAUCAUUUCCUCUUUAAACAAAAAAUAUGUUAUCCUACACAUUAGUGUCAAUCCAAUGGUUGUCUCUUAUCUGUCUAAAUAGCAAAAUCAUGAAAAUCAGCUGUUUUAUUUGCAUAGGACAACUAACCUGUCUGUGUAACUUUGUUUUUAUUUUAACUCUUACUAGAAAAUCUAAUCUUAAAACAUUUGAAUUCUAAACAUGUAAAAUGUGACAGCCUGCAAUUUUGUAGACAGUGAAGUAAUGGCUGCUAUUUAUAAAUGGAACAUCUAUCAAAAUAAGUAACUGUUUAUAAAAUUCAGUUUUUGUAGGGUUUUCCAAGGAAAAAUCACCUUGGUUGAAUGUUUCUCACUCAUUAAACUUUGCAGAAGUGAUUCAUAUUCAGUACUGUUUUUAAUCACUUUUUAAAAUAUAAGGACCGAAUGCAAGGAAACCAAAGUUUAUUAAUAAUUUUUAUAUAACUAAAAUAAAAUAGAUGUGGAGGGAUCUGUGAUCAUAUAAAAAGGGAGGGUUACUGAAAGAAUUUUAGCAAUAUAUUGAUUCAGGAAAAGGAGCUGUUUUAUAAAUGAUCAUUCACUGUUCCUAUGGUUCUAUGUAUCUUUCAAACCGAUACCUUUACUAUUUAAAGAGCGUAAAUAGUGAAAGUAAGAUGGUCAUACUUACUGACUUUAUCUAUUUAAGUUUGAUGGAGAUAAACUAUAUCUUGGCUAGUGGCUACUGUGUCUGUGAAUGUAACCAGUACUUCUUUAAGCUCUAUUCAGUAGGGUUCCAGCCACUGCUUUUUUGUUGUUUCUAGCCACUGUUUUUUUUUUCUUGUUUCCUUAUAAAACAGGUAAUAACCAAUCAUUUUGUGUUUGUAUUUCCAUUCCUUUUUAUUUCUGCCUUUGUGUAGACUGAUGAUUAAGUAGGCAAACUACUUCUACUUUCAAAGAGCCCCAAGGGCUUAAUGACCCCAUUUGUAACUGAGAAAUGAUUCUUGUUUUAGUAAUCAUUCUAUAAAUGAUACUGCUGGAUUGAUUGCCGUGGGUUGAUAGCUGGAGGAAUUGUUUUGGACAAUACUAACAUGUGAAUUUAUGUCUUAGUUUUAUUUGCAGUCUUGCUAAGUAAAAUGAGUCUUUGUAUCUACUUUUUUAUUAAAGUGAAAUUUAGCAAUAGUUAAUAUUAGGUGACAUAAAUAAAACAUCCCAGACUAGUGAGUUAAGUACAAGAUCUCUCUAAAAAUAAACAGAUGAAAAUCUAUCCCCAUUAUCGAUACAGAAUUUGUGAACGUGGCAUAAUUCUUGGUAGGUGCUAUAGAGAUUUAUCAUUUUAAACAGUUCACACACCACUGCAAUUCUGCUCCAAAGGACAAAGAUAUUUUCAAGUGAACCAAAAUUCAUUUUGAUAUCAGUUCAGUGGACGAACUCCCAGUCUUUACUCUGGAAAGCUGCCCAGCUUAGGGUUGCCAGAUAAAACAUAAGAUACCUAGUUAAAUAUGAAUUUCAACAAUGUACAAUUUUUAGUCUAAGUACUAUGUGUCCUAAACACUGCAUGAGACAUACUCAUACCAAAGUAUUUGUUGCUUAUGUGUAAUUCAUAUUUAACUGGGUAUCCUGUAUUUUUACUUGUUAAGUCCGGCAACCCUAGCCCAGGCUUUCUCAGGUUUUUUUUAACAGGGAUCCCAAGCUUUUUCUAUUGGUUUGAGAGCCUGCUACACAAAUAAUAUGAUCUUAACAAUUGAAUAGUUAUGUUAAGAGUGUAGUUACUGCAGUUAGACUGCCAAAGUUCAAAUCACUGCUCUACUACUUCUUAGGUGUGUGGUCUUGAAUAAGUUUUUUGACCUCUCUAAGCCUCAGUUUCUUCAUUAAUAAAAUGAGUUGCAUGGCUUAUAUGAAA